CGCUACUUCAGAUCAGUUACUUUUUUUUCUUUCUUUCUAAAUAGCCGGCCGAAUGCUCUUUUUCCAGUUCUGGCUAAGCUGUUAGCUGCAGCCGGGCGGCGACGCCUGCCAGGUACCUGGCUCCGUGAGCACCGCCCAAACUGGUCAGGCCAGUCCGUCCUGUGGCUGUUUCUGCCAGGACUCGCCCGAGUGUGUGUGUGCGCGUGUAUGUCAGAGACCCACCCUGCUCCCCUGCAACCGAGGUAGGUGGAAGGCAGUUGCAGGCACCAGCCUGGCAGUCAGGCCAGAUGGGUGGGGCUGAAUUAAUCUAACCUGGAAUUUCAACUUGGCCUGCACAACAGGUGAGGGAAAAAAGCAGCAGAGAGAACGGGCAGUUUGGCAACUUGGAAAUAUUCCUGAGCCCUGCCCCUUACCCCCUGCCUGGAACGUAGCCCAGGGUGACUCUUCAAAGUGUCUGCGCCGGGUUUUAGGGCUUAGUCGCCCCACGGCCCCCUCGAGGCUGUCCGAGGCCCUCCUGAACGCUGUCCUCCUCAGUUACCCUCCGCGACGCGCCCGUUCCCCCUCCUCUGGGAGGCAGGGCGGGGGUAUCGGAUUAGUCUUUGUUUUCGACGCGAAAGAAUCGAGCGCGGCGCGGGGGAGGCUGGUGAUGGCAGGGCCGUGGGGUCCACCUGGACAGGGCAUUCGGCCGUGACCCCUGCGAGGGUGCCCUUAGCCUCUGCCCCCGAGCAACCCCUUCUUGCCGGCCAGGCUGACUCGGCAGCACUGCCUUCUCCAGCGUCCAGACCCUGGAGGAAAAAUACCAGGAGAAACUGCUCACUCAGCUCUGCCCCCACCACACCCCUACCUGCUCAACUCAUGCCUGGGUCCAGGGUGGGUGAGGGUGAAGAACCCACCGGGCCAAGAUGAUCCCUUUUCUGAGGGCUGCUGCUGGUGUCCUCCCCCAGAUCCUGGGCCCCAGCAGGUGGGAGAGUGGCCCCCUACGGAGUCCGAUCAGACUGCUGCAGAGGAGGUGAAGAGGGGUUGAGAAGAGGCAUCCAUCCACGAGACUGAAGCCACUUGCCUUCACCCUUGUAGACUCUUGACUGUUCUAGGCGAGAAGGACCUGUUGGUGGCCUUUGGAGGUGGCAGGAAACGACUGUGGUUCUGCCCCAGCACCUAUGACCCCACCUCUGGCAGCAUCAUGAGCCAGUUUCAGGUGCCCCUGGCCGUCCAGCCGGACCUGCCAGGCCUUUAUGACUUCCCUCAGCGCCAGGUGAUGGUAGGGAGCUUCCCGGGGUCUGGGCUCUCCAUGGCUGGGAGUGAGUCCCAACUCCGAGGGGGUGGAGAUGGUCGAAAGAAACGGAAACGGUGUGGUACUUGUGAGCCCUGCCGGCGGCUGGAAAACUGUGGCGCUUGCACUAGCUGUACCAACCGCCGCACGCACCAGAUCUGCAAACUGCGAAAAUGUGAGGUGCUGAAGAAAAAAGUAGGGCUUCUCAAGGAGGUGGAAAUAAAGGCUGGUGAAGGAGCCGGGCCGUGGGGACAAGGAGCGGCUGUCAAGACAGGCUCAGAGCUCAGCCCAGUUGAUGGACCUGUUCCAGGUCAGAUGGACUCAGGGCCAGUGUACCAUGGGGACUCACGGCAGCUAAGCGCCUCAGGGGUGCCGGUCAAUGGUGCUAGAGAGCCCGCUGGACCCAGUCUGCUGGGGACUGGGGGUCCUUGGCGGGUAGACCAAAAGCCCGACUGGGAGGCUGCCCCAGGCCCAGCUCAUACUGCUCGCCUGGAAGAUGCCCACGAUCUGGUGGCCUUUUCGGCUGUGGCCGAAGCUGUGUCCUCUUAUGGGGCCCUUAGCACCCGGCUCUAUGAAACCUUCAACCGUGAGAUGAGUCGUGAGGCUGGGAACAACAGCAGGGGACCCCGGCCAGGGCCUGAGGGCUGCUCUGCUGGCAGCGAAGACCUUGACACACUGCAGACGGCCCUGGCCCUCGCGCGGCAUGGUAUGAAACCACCCAACUGCAACUGCGAUGGCCCAGAAUGCCCUGACUACCUCGAGUGGCUGGAGGGGAAGAUCAAGUCUGUGGUCAUGGAAGGAGGGGAGGAGCGGCCCAGGCUCCCAGGGCCUCUGCCUCCUGGUGAGGCCGGCCUCCCAGCACCAAGCACCAGGCCACUCCUCAGCUCAGAGGUGCCCCAGAUCUCUCCCCAAGAGGGCCUGCCCCUGUCCCAGAGUGCCCUGAGCAUUGCCAAGGAAAAAAACAUCAGCUUGCAGACCGCCAUUGCCAUUGAGGCCCUCACACAGCUCUCCUCUGCCCUCCCGCAGCCUUCUCAUUCCACCCCCCAGGCUUCUUGCCCCCUUCCUGAGGCCUUGUCACCUCCUGCCCCUUUCAGAUCUCCCCAGUCUUACCUCCGGGCUCCCUCAUGGCCUGUGGUUCCUCCUGAAGAGCACUCAUCUUUUGCUCCUGAUAGCUCUGCCUUCCCUCCAGCAACUCCUAGAACUGAGUUCCCUGAAGCCUGGGGCACUGACACCCCUCCAGCAACGCCCCGGAGCUCCUGGCCCAUGCCUCGCCCAAGCCCCGAUCCCAUGGCUGAACUGGAGCAGUUGUUGGGCAGCGCCAGUGAUUACAUCCAGUCAGUAUUCAAGCGGCCUGAGGCCCUGCCUACCAAGCCCAAGGUCAAGGUGGAGGCACCCUCUUCCUCCCCGGCCCCGGCCCCAUCCCCUGUACUUCAGAGGGAGGCUCCCACGCCAUCCUCGGAGCCCGACACCCACCAGAAGGCCCAGACCGCCCUGCAGCAGCACCUCCACCACAAGCGCAGCCUCUUCCUAGAACAGGUGCACGACACCUCCUUCCCUGCUCCUUCAGAGCCUUCUGCUCCUGGCUGGUGGCCCCCACCAAGUUCACCUGUCCCACGGCUUCCAGACAGACCACCCAAGGAGAAGAAGAAGAAGCUCCCAACACCAGCUGGAGGUCCCGUGGGAACGGAGAAAGCUGCCCCUGGGAUCAAGCCCAGUGUCCGAAAGCCCAUUCAGAUCAAGAAGUCCAGGCCCCGGGAAGCACAGCCCCUCUUCCCACCUGUCCGACAGAUUGUCCUGGAAGGGCUUAGGUCCCCAGCCUCCCAGGAAGUGCAGGCUCAUCCACCGGCCCCUCUGCCUGCCUCACAGGGCUCUGCUGUGCCCCUGCCCCCAGAACCUUCUCUUGCGCUAUUUGCACCUAGUCCCUCCAGGGACAGCCUGCUGCCCCCUACUCAGGAAAUGAGGUCCCCCAGCCCCAUGACAGCCUUGCAGCCAGGCUCCACUGGCCCUCUUCCCCCUGCCGAUGACAAGCUGGAAGAGCUCAUCCGGCAGUUUGAGGCUGAAUUUGGAGAUAGCUUUGGGCUUCCCGGCCCCCCUUCUGUGCCCAUUCAGGACCCCGAGAACCAGCAAACAUGUCUCCCAGCCCCUGAGAGCCCCUUUGCUACCCGUUCCCCCAAGCAAAUCAAGAUUGAGUCUUCGGGGGCUGUGACUGUGCUCUCAACCACCUGCUUCCAUUCAGAGGAGGGAGGACAGGAGGCCACACCCACCAAGGCUGAGAACCCACUCACACCCACCCUCAGUGGCUUCUUGGAGUCACCUCUUAAGUACCUGGACACACCCACCAAGAGUCUGCUGGACACACCUGCCAAGAGAGCCCAGGCCGAGUUCCCCACCUGCGAUUGCGUCGAACAAAUAGUGGAGAAAGAUGAAGGUCCAUAUUAUACUCACUUGGGAUCUGGCCCCACGGUCGCCUCUAUCCGGGAACUCAUGGAGGAGCGGUAUGGAGAGAAGGGGAAAGCCAUCCGGAUCGAGAAGGUCAUCUACACGGGGAAGGAGGGAAAGAGCUCCCGCGGUUGCCCCAUUGCAAAGUGGGUGAUCCGCAGGCACACGCUGGAGGAGAAGCUACUCUGCCUGGUGCGGCACCGGGCAGGCCACCACUGCCAGAACGCUGUGAUCGUCAUCCUCAUCCUGGCCUGGGAGGGCAUUCCCCGUAGCCUCGGAGACACCCUCUACCAGGAGCUCACCGACACCCUCCGGAAGUAUGGGAACCCCACCAGCCGGAGAUGCGGCCUCAACGAUGACCGGACCUGCGCUUGCCAAGGCAAAGACCCCAACACCUGUGGUGCCUCCUUCUCCUUUGGUUGUUCCUGGAGCAUGUACUUCAACGGCUGCAAGUAUGCUCGGAGCAAGACACCUCGCAAGUUCCGCCUCGCAGGGGACAAUCCCAAAGAGGAAGAAGUGCUCCGGAAGAGUUUCCAGGACCUGGCCACCGAAGUCGCUCCCCUGUACAAGCGACUGGCCCCUCAGGCCUAUCAGAACCAGCUGGGGCCUCUCAGCCAGAAAACCUCCCUCCUGCAGUCGAAGGGCAAGGUGACCAACGAGGAAAUAGCGAUUGACUGCCGUCUGGGGCUGAAGGAAGGACGGCCCUUCGCGGGGGUCACGGCCUGCAUGGACUUCUGUGCCCACGCCCACAAGGACCAGCAUAACCUCUACAAUGGGUGCACCGUGGUCUGCACCCUGACCAAGGAAGACAAUCGCUGCGUGGGCAAGAUUCCCGAGGAUGAGCAGCUGCAUGUUCUCCCCCUGUACAAGAUGGCCAACACGGAUGAGUUUGGUAGCGAGGAGAACCAGAAUGCAAAGGUGGGCAGCGGAGCCAUCCAGGUGCUCACCGCCUUCCCCCGCGAGGUCCGACGCCUGCCCGAGCCUGCCAAGUCCUGCCGCCAGCGGCAGCUGGAAGCCAGAAAGGCAGCAGCCGAGAAGAAGAAGAUUCAGAAGGAGAAGCUGAGCACUCCGGAGAAGAUCAAGCAGGAGGCCCUGGAGCUGGCGGGCAUUACGUCGGACCCAGGCCUGUCUCUGAAGGGUGGAUUGUCCCAGCAAGGCCUGAAGCCCUCCCUCAAGGUGGAGCCGCAGAACCACUUCAGCUCCUUCAAGUACAGCGGCAACGCGGUGGUGGAGAGCUACUCGGUGCUGGGCAACUGCCGGCCCUCCGACCCUUACAGCAUGAACAGCGUGUACUCCUACCACUCCUACUAUGCACAGCCCAGCCUGACCUCCGUCAAUGGCUUCCACUCCAAGUACGCUCUCCCGUCUUUUAGCUACUAUGGCUUUCCAUCCAGCAACCCCGUCUUCCCCUCUCAGUUCCUGGGUCCUGGUGCCUGGGGGCACAGUGGCAGCAGUGGCAGUUUUGAGAAGAAGCCAGACCUCCACGCUCUGCACAACAGCCUGAGCCCGGCCUACGGUGGUGCUGAGUUUGCCGAGCUGCCCAGCCAGGCUGUUCCCACAGACGCCCACCACCCCACUCCUCACCACCAGCAGCCUGCGUACCCAGGCCCCAAGGAGUAUCUGCUUCCCAAGGCCCCCCUACUCCACUCAGUGUCCAGGGACCCCUCCCCCUUUGCCCAGAGCUCCAACUGCUACAACAGAUCCAUCAAGCAAGAGCCAGUAGACCCGCUGACCCAGGCUGAGCCUGUGCCCAGAGACGCUGGCAAGAUGGGCAAGACACCUCUGUCCGAGGUGUCUCAGAAUGGAGGACCCAGUCACCUUUGGGGACAGUACUCAGGAGGCCCAAGCAUGUCCCCCAAGAGGACUAACGGUGUGGGUGGCAGCUGGGGUGUGUUCUCGUCUGGGGAGAGUCCUGCCAUCGUCCCUGACAAGCUCAGUUCCUUUGGGGCCAGCUGCCUGGCCCCUUCCCACUUCACAGAUGGCCAGUGGGGGCUGUUCCCCGGUGAGGGGCAGCAGGCAGCUUCCCACUCUGGAGGACGGCUGCGAGGCAAACCGUGGAGCCCCUGCAAGUUUGGGAACAGCACCUCGGCCUUGGCUGGGCCCAGCCUGACUGAGAAGCCGUGGGCGCUGGGGGCAGGGGAUUUCAACUCGGCCCUGAAAGGUAGUCCUGGGUUCCAAGACAAGCUGUGGAACCCCAUGAAAGGAGAGGAGGGCAGGAUUCCAGCCGCAGGGGCCAGCCAGCUGGACAGGGCCUGGCAGUCCUUUGGUCUGCCCCUGGGAUCCAGCGAGAAGCUGUUUGGGGCUCUGAAGUCAGAGGAGAAGCUGUGGGACCCCUUCAGCCUGGAGGAGGGGCCGGCUGAGGAGCCCCCCAGCAAGGGAGCGGUGAAGGAGGAGAAGGGCGGUGGUGGUGCGGAGGAGGAAGAGGAGGAGCUGUGGUCGGACAGUGAACACAACUUCCUGGACGAGAACAUCGGCGGCGUGGCCGUGGCCCCAGCCCACGGCUCCAUCCUCAUCGAGUGUGCCCGGCGGGAGCUGCACGCCACCACGCCGCUUAAGAAGCCCAACCGCUGCCACCCCACCCGCAUCUCGCUGGUCUUCUACCAGCACAAGAACCUCAACCAGCCCAACCACGGGCUGGCCCUCUGGGAAGCCAAGAUGAAGCAGCUGGCGGAGAGGGCACGGGCACGGCAGGAGGAGGCUGCCCGGCUGGGCCUGGGCCAGCAGGAGGCCAAGCUCUACGGGAAGAAGCGCAAGUGGGGGGGCACUGUGGUUGCUGAGCCCCAGCAGAAAGAGAAGAAGGGGGUCGUCCCCACCCGGCAGGCACUGGCUGUGCCCACAGACUCGGCGGUCACCGUGUCCUCCUAUGCCUACACGAAGGUCACUGGCCCCUACAGCCGCUGGAUCUAGGUGCCAGGGAGCCAGCGUACCUCAGCGUCGGGCCUGGCCCGAGCUGUCUCUGUGGUGCUUUUGCCCUCAUACCUGGGGGCGGGUUGGGGGUGCAGAAGUCUUUUUAUCUCUAUAUACAUAUAUAGAUGCGCAUAUCAUAUAUAUGUAUUUAUGGUCCAAACCUCAGAACUGACCCGCCCCUCCCUUACCCCCACUUCCCCAGCACUUUGAAGAAGAAACUACGGCUGUCGGGUGAUUUUUCCGUGAUCUUAAUAUUUAUAUCUCCAAGUUGUCCCCCCCCCUUGUCUGGGGGGUUUUUAUUUUUAUUUUCUCUUUGUUUUUAAAACUCUAUCCUUGUAUAUCACAAUAAUGGAAAGAAAGUUUAUAGUAUCCUUUCACAAAGGAGUAGUUUUAAAUUCCAUUUAAAAUGUGUAUUUAUUGGAUUUUUUAAAAGCGACAAUAGUAAUGGUAAAGGAUGGGCAGGAAAGGCCAGUAGUGCUCCCCCGCCCAGUCUCGCUGGGUCUGGCGAGCCAAGCCCCUCGGGCGCUGGCGAGGUCCUCAGCCAUCUGCCCCUCGAGAGCCAAGCGCGGACGGUAGCCACCCAGUUCAUCCCUCCCGACAUACACCCCUUCCCUUUGGGGAAGGGAGCCUCAGGACAGCUUCUGUCCUCUCUGAUAGGAUGGGAGAGUCUGCAGAAAACCAUCUGGGGUCCCUUUUCCAGUCCCCGGCUUGGAGUCGAAGGGCAGAUGCACCCCAGGCCAGCCCCACGAGAUGCUGGCAUAGCUUUCCCCAGAAACCAGGUUGGAAGUAGAUGGCUUCAAGCUUGCUAGUCUCCACACUGAAUCCUCUGUCCGUUAUUUAUGGAGUCACACGAUGUCAUGGUUCACUAGGCAGCACCUCACGCUGGAGCUGGAGUGCGAGGUUCUUAGGGGCCGUGCCCACCAUGUUGCCAAGCCAAUGCAUGCUGAGCUGAAGGAAUUUGUCUUAGUGGCAGUUUUUUAAAAAAUGCCCCCAAAGUCUAUGCUGAUACUGAAAAAGGGCUACUGUAUCUUUAAAAACAGGAAGUUGAACCCAAGCUGUGAAAAGCCAGUGGUGCUCUGUGCAUGGUGCUGUGCGGAGCCUGGUGCUGUAGUGUUGUGCUGGGACUUUCUUGACUCUUGGGCAGGUCACAUCCUACAGGAGCUCAGCAGACCAGUGUAACAACAGUUAAUGCAUCUAUCCUGAUCCCUGAAUUUCCACAUUGGACAAUGGUGCAUGCCUCACACCUGAGCCUGCUUCCUCCAUGCUGUCAUUGGGUUCGGGGGCCUACACUUAACAAUUUUAAAGUGCAAGAGUCAAACAUUUUCAACAGGUUGCUAUAAUUUUCCUCCCUAAUUGGUGCCAUUUCUCCAUUUGAUCAUUUUCUUUUUUUCCUUUCUCCCCUCUUCAUCCACUUUAAUAUAGCUGUUCUGAAAUUCUGGUGCAUUCAUUCGGUUCUUUGAAAUGAGAAUGUGGUGCUUAAUUUUUGUGACGUUGUCGAGAGAGGUUGGGCCUGAUGGGAGCAACACUCAUCAUCACCAAGUCAAACUUUGUUGGAGUGUUGGUUUUUCUUGUGAUAUUAGCAGAAAUGAUCUCAUGCUAGCCAUGUGGAUGUGUGUGUGGUGAAUGGGGGGCUUCAUCAGGACACACAGAGGGGAAUGUGGCCACACGGUGGAUGACCACCAAGCCCUGAGAUGAACAGGUAUUUACUGAGCAGUUGUAUUCAGAUAUGGGUCUUCAUGAAUCAUGUUUAACAAUCAGAUGACCGCUAUAGGCAAGUUCCUGAGCUUCCGGGUGCCUUGAGUAAGAGCUGAGAACCGGCCUGCUGGGUGUUUACUGUAUCUGUUUGGAAGCACUGGCGGAGGGUCGUUGUAAGAUGUCCUGAGCAUUUAUGUGGUCUGGUUUUAACUGUAAAUAGUGAAAGAUUUUUUUAAGCACUUUUGCCUAGAUUUAAACAGCAACUUGAAAAAAAAAGUAUGUUUUAACAUGUAAUUGUGGGAGAAAUUGUAAAUAGUAGCCGAAUAUUUAAUGUGCUUUGUCUAUCCUCCACUUUUACCAUAUUCUGUAAAGUUGCAUUUAUUUUACAGGACAAAAAAAUGAAAUAUUAUUGCUUUUGAAAUAAAUACCCAAGAGCUUAUCAGGACUUAGAAUUAUUCAGAACUCAGAUUUAUAGGAAAACCUCUGACCUUCAGUUUGACAAGCUAAAGGAAGCAGAGUCUUUAAUGAGCAUGCUAAUUUUCUAGUUUUGAGGAAAAAUUGGGUCCUUUAAAUGCUAUUUUGCUUAUCGCAUCAGUACUUUUAUGCAGGUCUCAUUUGACUCCGUGCUUAGGUAGAUGCGGGGGUGCCUUGAAAACUUCAUUUUAAAUGAUCUUAAGCAAGAAAUACAAUAUUUUACGAAACAUUUGGAGAAUGUGACCGUCUGUAUGACCCGUGGAAGCCCCAGGUUGGCUGUUGGUUUGGAAGGUCCCGAGUGUAACCCAGGUGAUUCUGAUACUUGGCAUGUGUGAAUCUUCCUGAUGUAUGUUAAAUAAACUCUUCCCCUCAUCACCCUUUGGUAGGAAAGCCAUUAGAUGAAAGGAGAAACCAAUACAAGCUAAAAGCAUGCGACGUCUGUCCCCCAGCCCAAACAGCCUUGGUUCAUCAGUUUCUGCAGUAGGAGAUAGGCUGCUGAGAGGUGAGUCAAGAGGCAGUCUCCAUUGGAUGUCCCCACUCCCCGCAGAAUGGCGUUUCCAGAGUUAGGCGGUGUGGUUGCCGUGCUCAAGCCCAUGCUGAUUUGUACACUACAUGUCUAACCUACCUCAAAUCUCAGUCAUUAAAAUUAGCAUGCUUUAGACAUAUAUUUAAAAAGUAACUAUGCACAGCUCUUUAUCCCCCCCUUGCUGCUGAAGCUUUCUUAAAGAGAAAAAUCAAAUUUUUAUUUUUUACUGGCACUAUCAUUUUUUAAGUCCUAAAGAUGAUUAACAGACAUUUUUAUCAUGAGAAGAAAAAUAAAGCCAUUGCAACUAAAGAACCUAACAGCAUGACCAAGUUCGAAGAGUCAUAUUAUAGCAACGGAAAUCGAUGGCGUCUUAGUCAUCUCCCCAGUGUGCCCUGUCCACGGACACCAUCCACGUGCAGUGCAAACAUUUGGUUCCUUUUCUGCUCUGUUUUGUUUUCCCUGCCUGUUGCGUGCAAGGGAAGUGCUUGUAAAGUUCUGUGCUACGAGAUUUUUAAAAUAAAAAUCGCUUCGCAGCAGGUUCUCACAAAAUAACUGGUGCUAGCUCAAGAAAUCAUCAUCUGACCAUCAGAAAUCUUGACUAAAGGUGUUGCAUGGAUUUGGGGGUCUUUCGGUUUUUGGUUUUGGGUCUGGCUUUUAGCAGGGCCAAUGUUUCCCACACCCCGGCUUCAUGGGUACUGCUUUGCCUUCUCACCAAGGUGACGAUGGUGUGCGUGGAAAGAGAUGAUACCCCACCGCCCCCUCUUGGUCCUUCCACCAGCCUCUUUUGGGAACAGUAGUUUGCAGAGCAAGGGAUUUUUAAAGCGCUAAAGCAAGGAAAGAAGUAGCAGAGCUUAACUGCUUUGUACCACACAGCAGUAGAUGUGCAAGGACGGUUGACAAUGAGUCGAUGAUAACCUAAUUUCAUUGAGAGAAACCCAGCCAGACUUGCUUCUAGAGGUUUAAUCACCAUGAGAUCUCAAACCAAGGCAAAGCUGGUGGAAAACUAUAUGAUAUCCCUGACGUGCCUCAACCAGUAUCUCUUUCCUUUUGUUACUGAAGUGUGUUUUAUGGACUAGGAAGCAUUUUUAUGAAUUGAAAUAGUCUAAAUAAAAUGGUGCUAUGGUGUUUUAAUGUGACUGUCCCUGAUCCUGUCUUGCUGAGGUGCUAUCAACGUUCUGAAACCACAACCAACCAAAAACAAGGUGGGCUCCAGUCUCUUGGCUUUUUUUUUUCCCUCCCCUCUUUUGGUGCUGUCUUAGACCCGUUUACCGUGCUAUAAUCUGCUCUGAGCAGUGUUGUGUUGUGUUGUAUUGUUCUUCCCUUGGUGGCCAAACAAAGCAAGUCGAGAAGGCAGCUAUCUCCCUUUCUGUGAUCGGGAGUGGGCCUGCCUGGCUUGGCAGGUGCUUUUUGGUUCCACACCUGUCUUCUCAGGCUUGAUGUGAAAGAAAGGGCGAAGGGUUUUUUGAGUUUUUGUUUUUGAGGAAGGGGAGUUGGGUACUUCUGCCUCUCCUAGCAUGAUAGGCAUUCUCAUAGCCAGGGACAGAUUUUCUCCUGCAGCCCAGGGUGCUAAGCAGACAUCUCUGGGAGUCCCAAGGGCACACCAAGGGAGACCAGAUGGAUCUCCUUCCUCCCCUGGCACUGGCUGGGACCAUGGUGGGCAGGGGCUUCAUUCUCUGACCCAGCGUUGCUUCUGCCUCUCAUUGGUAACCCCUUAUGUUCGGACUAAAGGAAGGAGCUUUCUUUGCUCACUCGAUGCCACUGAGGCUGCUUUUUAGUUGGUGCUAACCUAAAUUUCUUCUUGGGUCCACAGAAGUUGAUGUUUUAAAAACUCACCAGGAAGCUCCAUUUUGUGUCAUCCACUGUCACAAUAAUUUUUUUAAAUACCUCAAAAACAGGACAUCAUGACAACUUCAGUAAAGUAGAUUCCAUGAGGGUCUGAUACCUGCAGGUUGUCCGUCUGAUGACAUACUUGACCUUGAAAAAUCUGGGGUCAUUUUGUUUUUCAUUCUUCAGCAGUUAAGAUAGCGGAACGCCGAAAGGAAGGAGCGUAGUUGGCUGUAUUUCAUGUUUAAGUUUUGCUUUUGAAUAAAAUGUGAAUUUCCUAUGCCCAUCUCAUUGAGCUUUCUCAGUCAUUGUUGCUGUCAUUUGAAAUGACUCCCUCAAAACCUAGUUUUAUUAGCCAGCUGCCUCUGCUGUAGUACAUGGCCAACUUCAACAUACCCUGGACCAAAACAUUUUUGAGGUGCAUACCCCCAACAUAAGUUACACAGUCCCACAUCCAGGUGCACAGAGUGCGAGUGCACUCCGCGAGUGCGGGGGGAGGGGCGGCCCCCUCUGGUGCUCCCAGCCCUUCCUCCUGCAGAGCUGCAGGCAAGAGCAGAGCAAUAGGCUUCUCCCCUGAGCAGAGACCGCAGCACAGAAAUGCAAGGUCUAAAGUUGCUUUUUGCCUAAGAAUCAGCGAGCGAUUUGGCCUACUUCCUCAUUGGCUUCUAUUCUGAUAUCAGGGAUGCUUUUUGUAGUGGUAUUGUUUGCUCCCUCUUCGCGUUUUGACUACCCGUCAUUCAGGGGUAACUCAUCACUCUUCACACGGGGAUUUAAAUUAAGAAACUAAUUGGCUCAUGUGAACAUUCCAAAUUUUCUUGGUUUCAAUACCCUUUUUUUUCUUUUGAGGGGAAAAGAGGGGAGAAAAACAGGAGUGAUGUCAUUUCUUUUUCAUGUAUUCCAAUUAAAGAAACAAGGGCAGGUCGUAUAAUGGCAUAUUAAUACAUUAGACUUAAUCUAGAACCCCUGUAGCUUUUUGAUGUGUUUUAUUUCUUAUCUCUUUGAAUUCCUGUUUGGUUACUUGGCUUCCAAUGGAGGUGAACUUAACAACCAUACUUGAAUAUUCCGUCUUGACUUUGUAAACUGUGGCUACUUGAAAUGAAGUUUAUCUGGGGUUGAUGGAUGAAUGGUAGAUUUUUGCAAUGUCUCAAGGCAAUAGGAUGUGUAUUAAACUGUAGAUAUUCUUAGUACAGUAAAUUUAUGCUGAUAAUUUUAUUUUGUAUAAUUUUUACCUUUUUGUUAAUAUUUUUUCCUUCCACUUUAUUGGUUUGCCUCCUGAGCUACCCCUCCUUACCCUCCCUUCUCCCUCAGUGUUUCAGUAAAUUUAAUUUAGGGUGCCUAGAAAUUGCAAGUAUGUAUCCUUUUUGAUUUGUAUUUUAUUAUAAUUUACACAAACAACUGGGUUUGUGAACUGUAUUACUCCUGGUAUCUUUAAAAUAUUGUGGGUGUUUUAAUAAAUUUUAUAUUUAUUUUUUGCACUCAAA